AACGAAACGGUAACCAGCCCUGGGAAGCCCGCAAGAGGCCUCAGCGGUGGCCGUCCGAGAGCCGAGAGGUGAGGGUGCCCCCGCCUCACCUGCAGAGGGGCCGUUCCGGGCUCGAACCCGGCACCUUCCGGAAAAUGGCGGCUGCCAGGCCCAGCCUGGGCCGAGUCCUCCCAGGAUCCUCUGUCCUGUUCCUGUGUGACAUGCAGGAGAAGUUCCGCCACAACAUCGCCUACUUCCCACAGAUCGUCUCAGUGGCUGCCCGCAUGCUCAAGGUGGCCCGGCUGCUUGAGGUGCCAGUCAUGCUGACGGAGCAGUACCCACAAGGCCUGGGCCCCACGGUGCCCGAGCUGGGGACUGAGGGCCUUCGGCCGCUGGCCAAGACCUGCUUCAGCAUGGUGCCUGCCCUGCAGCAGGAGCUGGACAGUCGGCCCCAGCUGCGCUCUGUGCUGCUCUGUGGCAUUGAGGCACAGGCCUGCAUCUUGGACCCCCGUUCUUAUCCGGGGUUGGCCCUGACCUCUCUCUACCCACAGAACACGACCCUGGACCUCCUAGACCGGGGGCUGCAGGUCCAUGUGGUGGUGGACGCCUGCUCCUCACGCAGCCAGGUGGACCGGCUGGUGGCUCUGGCCCGCAUGAGACAGAGUGGUGCCUUCCUCUCCACCAGCGAAGGGCUCAUUCUGCAGCUUGUGGGCGAUGCCGUCCACCCCCAGUUCAAGGAGAUCCAGAAACUCAUCAAGGAGCCCGCCCCAGACAGCGGACUGCUGGGCCUCUUCCAAGGCCAGAACUCCCUCCUCCACUGAACUCCAACCCUGCCUUGAGGGAAGACCACCCUCCUGUCACCCGGACCUCAGUGGAAGCCCGUUCCCCCCAUCCCUGGAUCCCAAGAGUGGUGCGAUCCACCAGGAGUGCCGCCCCCUUGUGGGGGGGGCAGGGUGCUGCCUUCCCAUUGGACAGCUGCUCCCGGAAAUGCAAAUGAGACUCCUGGAAACUGGGUGGGAAUUGGCUGAGCCAAGAUGGAGGCGGGGCUCGGCCCCGGGCCACUUCACGGGGCGGGAAGGGGAGGGGAAGAAGAGUCUCAGACUGUGGGACACGGACUCGCAGAAUAAACAUAUAUGUGGCUGUG